ACGGGUCUGCUUCUGCACUGGUGUAAUCAAAACCUCGUCCUUGAGAGAGGCCCCCAGGAACAAGUCAAUGAUCUCAGAUUCCUUGAUGGGCAGGGAGAAGAGAUAGAUCUCCUCCAGGGACUAGAUCUUCAUGUCCUUGACCAGGCAGCCCAGCUUGGUAACGGGCAUCCACUUCUUAUCCUCGGCCUUGCCUCUCAGAGCUCCGCGGCCCCGGCCCCGGAUGCCACUGCCGAAAUCUCCGCGGAAGCCACUGCGGUUCCCCAUCCCAGGGUCCCCAGGGCCUCUGGACCCCCGCGCUGCACCUGCGUCAUCAGCCAUUUGGUGUUUUCUUGGAGAAGAAGCUAUACCUUUUAAUAUUUAUCUUUUAGUUAUCUCCAUGUGAUUAUGUAUUAUCUCCAUAUGAUUAUAUAUUGUGUUUUUACUGGAUUAGCAUUCAUGUUGAACAUACCGCCUUUGUGGGCUUUCAUCUGUGAAAUAAUUCUCAGUCAUUUAAUUCAUUUGCAUAGUAAAUGCAAAUGUUUGCUUUGUUUCUCUCUUUUUGUUUUAGGCAUACUUUAUACACGAAUCCUUUUUUACAUGGAGGGAUUGGUAAUAUUUCCUUUCAGAUGGUGGUUUAUCUUUUAAAUUUAUUCUACUUAGAUGAACUCUUCCUAAAUUUUUUAUUUUUUUAGAUAAUGUCCAGCUCUGUCACCCAGGCUGGACUGCAGUGGCAUAAUCAGCUCACUGCAGCCUCAAACUCCUGGGCUCCCAAGUAGCUGGGACUAUAGGCAUGUGCCACCACACUUGGCUAAUUUUUUAAUUUUGUGUAGCCAGAGGGUCUGCCAUGUUGCCGGGCUGGUUUCAAAUUCCUGGCCUCAAGAGUUCCUCUUGCCUUGGCCUCCCACAGUACUGGGAUUAUAGAUGUGAGUCACUAUGCCUGCUUCUUCUUAAUGUAAUUAGAGUUCAAUUUACCAGACUUCUCCUUUGGAAGCUACUUUAUUUUCUUAUAUAAGAAGACUCUUGUUAAAUAAGAAAAACAUUUUUUCUGGCUGGGCGUGGUGGCUUAUGCCUGUAAUCCCAGCACUUUGGGAGGCCGAGGAGGGCGGAUCAUGAGGUCAGAAGAUCAUGACCAUCCUGGCUAAUACGGUGAAACCCCGUCUCUACUAAAAAUACAAAAAAAUUAGCCAGGCGUGGUGGUGGAUGCCUGUAAUCCCAGCUACUCAGGAGGCUGAGGCAGGAGAAUGGCAUGAACUCGGGAGGCGGAGCUUGCAGUGAGCCAAGAUCACGCCACUGCACUCAAGUCUGGGUAGACAGUGCGAGACUCUGUCUCAAAAAGAAAAAAAAAUUUCUGUAAUUUCUAAAAGUGUGCUGCUUUUGUCUUUCAUAGGUGUUGUAUAUUCUUCUAAUUUAAUCUUUAGGUCUGUCUCUUGAAACUGGCUAUAAACUUUAUCUCUGCUCUGGUGUGUCUCCAGGGAUUUGGUUGGGGAUGGUUACAUUGCGCCUUUCAUGGGAUACUUUUGUUUACCAAAAAUAAGGCCAUUGAGGCAGAUACAAUUUGAUAAAGUUUUAUUGUAAGCCAAAUUUGAGGAUCAACUUGAGAAGACACACCAACAAAUUUGGAUGUGUUCCAAAAUUGAUUACAAGUUGGAUGCCUUUAUGAGAAAGUUUAGGAGAAGCUGGAGGACUAUUCAUACCGGAAUUGUCAUUUUCCUUGAAGGGUACAAUAUAGACGUUACAAUCAUUGCCUAUAGAUGACAGCUGACAGGCUAAAAUGUUCUAAGUGGAAGACAAUCAGCAAAACAUGAUUCAGAAAUAAAUCAGUGUCUUUUUUGAUGUUAGUAGAUAACGUUAAUCAUAUCAACAGUUUGAAGAACUCACAAUAAGAUUUGAGGGACUCAUGAUAAGAUCCUUUACUCACAGACAGAAUGUAAGCCAUUUAAUUAGAAGACUUCUCGCCAGGCGUGGUAUCUCAUGCCUGUAAUCCCAGCACUUUGGGAGGCCUAGGUGGGCGGAUCACCUCAGGUCAGAAAUUCGAGACCAGCCUGACCAACAUGGCGAAAUCCUGUCUCUACUAAAAAAUACAAAAAUUAGCCGGGCAUGGUAGCGGACACCUAUAAUCCCAGCUGCUCGAGAGGCUGAGGCAGGAGAAUUGUUUGAACCUGGGAGGCGGAGGUUGCAGUGAGCUGAGAUCGUGCUAUUGCACUCCAGCCUGGGUGACAGAGCAAGACUCCGUCUCAAAAAAAAAAAAAAAAAAGAAGACUUCUCCAAGUGGGUUGAUUUGGAAACCUGCCAAAUGUGACCUGUAGGUUAUCACUUCUUUAUCUUGGCAGGGAGCUUAAUGCCUAUAUGUGAGACCAGUGACCUGAUUCCUGUAGACUUCAAAGCCUAAUGUGUGUAGAGAAAGAGUCUACCUCUCUUAGUCACUUAGGACUGCUAUACCAGAUUGCCAUACACUGCAUGCCUUAGACAACAAACAUUCAUUUCUCAAAGGUGUAGAGGCUGAAAGUCCAAUAUCAAGCAGAUGAGGCCUCUGGUAAGGGCCUGCUACCUGGUUUGAAGAUGGCAGUCUAACCCUUAUGUCCUCACAUGGUGGAGAUAUGUCUGUAAUGUCUGUCUAGUUUUGGUGUUAGGGCAAUGUUGGCCUUAUAAAAUGGAAUAGAAGGUGUUUCCUCUGCUUCUGUUUUCUGGAAGAGAUUGUAGAGAAUUGGUAUCAUUUCUUCCAUAAACGCUUGCCAGAAUUCAGCAGUGAAAUCGUUCUGACCUGUUGCUUAUUUUUUCUGGGACAUUUAUUAUUUAUUAAUAUCUUCAGUAGAUACAGGCCUAUUCAUAUUACUUAGGUCUCUUUUUGUGAGUUUUGGUAGAUAGUGUCUUUCAAGGAAUUGGUCCAUUCUGUGUAAUUUUAUCAAAUAUGUGGGCACUUAGUUGUUCCUAAUAGUUUUUUAUGGUCAUUUUACUGUCCAUGGGAGUAGUAGUGAUGGCUCCUCUUUUUUCUGAGUUAACUUGGCUAUGGGCUUAUGAAUUUUAAUGAUGUUUCCAAAGAACCAUCUGUUGGUUUGUUGAUGUUUUCUACUGAUUUCUUCAUUGCUAUUUCAUUAAUAUCUCUUCUCAUCGUUACUUUCCUCUGUUUGAUUUACAUUAAUCUUGUCAUUUUUCUCUAGUUUCCUAAAAUGGAAGGUUAGGGUGUUGAUUUUAAACCUUUACUUUCUAGGAAAUGCAUUUAAUUCUUUAAAUUUCCCUCAAAGCACUGCCUUUACUCCAUUCCAAAGAUUUUGCUAAGAUAUAUCACUUUUCAUCAACAUUGCAAUAUUUACAUUUUGCUUGACAAUUCUCCUUGAAGUUUGUGUAGUUGAGAAGUUUGUGGCUUCAAUCUCCACUUUGUUGAGGUUUUUCAACUAUGCUUCUGUUACUAAUUUUUACAUUAAUUCUAAUAUGAUUUGAUCGCAUACUUUAAAAAAUUUGUUCAAGUGUGUUUUAUGGCUGAGAAUAUUGUUCAUCUUGGUGAAUAUUUCAUGUAGGCUUGAGAAGAAUAUGUAUGCUGUUGUUGAAUGAAUGAUUCUAUAAAUAUGUUUCAAUUAAAUCCAGUUGAUUGAUAGUGCUGUUGAGUUCAGCUAUAUCAUUAGUGAUUUUCUGCAGAACUGAUCUGUCAAUUAUUGAUAGAGGUGAGUUGUUUUCCCUCAACUAUAAUCCUAGAUUUGUGUAUUUUGCCUUGUGGUUUUAUAUGUUUUUGCAUUAUGUAUUUUGAUGCUCUGUUUUAUGGGCAUAGAUGUUAAGGAUUAUUAUGUCGUGUAGGAUUGACUUCUUGAUCAUUAUGAAAUCUCUCUAUCCCUUGUAAUUUUUAAAAAAUCUAAAACCUGAUUUGUCUGAAUGUAAUAUAGGUCUUCCAAAUUUCUUUUGAUCAGGGCUAGAAUGGCAUGUAUUUCUUCAUACUUGUGUAUUUAAUGUAUCUGUGUCUUUCUGUUUAAAAUACUUUUUAAAAAUAUAGUUUGGGGCCUUGUUUUUUAUUUCACUCUGCCAGUCCCUUUCUUUUUUACUGGUGAAUAUAGAUAAUACACAUUUAAGUGGCAGUUGGCAUAAUUGGAUUCAGAUAAACAUGUAUAUUAUUGUUUUCUAUUUGUUGUUCUUCUCUGUGUUUUUUAACUUCUCUUUUCUGCCCUUUUUCCUUUUAGCUGAGCAUUCUAUAUGAUUUUAUUUUCUAUAUUAUAUAUCUAUAUAGUCUACUUUUUCUUAGAUUCUAUUAGUGAGUUCCCCAGAGUUUGUAGUAUAGCAUUCACAACUAAUGGGCCUUCAAUUUCAAAUAGUACUAUACUGGCUUCAGGAAUAGUGCUGGUAUAAUAGACAGUUCCGAAGUGUGAUAGACUGUUCUUCCUCCCAUCACAUAUAACAUUACUUUCAUUCAUUAGUUCAACUGGGAGCUAUAAACUACUGAAUACAUUGUUGAUAUUAUUAUUUUUUCUUUUGAGACAGAAUCUCACUCUGUUUCCCAGGCUGGAGUGCAAUGGCAUGAUCUCGGCUCACUGCAACCUCUGCCUCCUGGGUUCAAGCAAUUGUCCUGCCUCAGCCUCCCUAGUAGCUGGGAUUACAGCUGUGCACCACCACGCCCAGCUAAUUUGAUAUUAUUAUUUUGAAUAAACCUAUAUCUAUUAGAUCAGAUAGGUAUAAGAAGAGUAAAGAAUUUUUUGUGCCUUCAUUUAAUUGUUUCCUAACACUCUUCAUAUAUAUGUGUGUGUAUACACACACACACACACACACACACAAUCUGAAUUUCUAACCCAUAUCAUUUUUUUCUUUCUGAUGAACUUCUUUUUUUUUUUAACUCAGACCAGGUAAUUUCAAUUGUUUUACCUUCAUUUUAGUUUUUUUUUUCCACUGGUUGCUCACAUCUGUUGAAUACCUUUAGUGAUGUUUUCAUUUAAGUUGUUGUAUCUUGCAGCUGCAGAAAUUCUAUAUGGCUCAAUUUUUAACAUAUUUUGGUAUUAUUUUAUCCCUACAUCAAUUUUCUGGUUUUCUCUUAGUUCUUUGUUUAUUAUUGUCUUUACUAAGUUAAAUAUAUUUAAGACAGUUGCUUUACUGUUUUUAUUCAGUAAAUCCAGUGUCUGAGGUUUCUCAGAUUUAUCUCAAAUUGUUUCCAUUAAUGAGUCGUAUUUUCAUGUUUCUCUGUUUUAUUUAUUUCUCUGGGGUUUUUUUGGGGGUGGGGGUAUUGAAAAGGAGACAUUUGAAUGUUAUAACUGGGUAACUCUGGAAAUCAGAUUUUUGCCCCUUAAUUGUUUGGUAUUCUUGCUUGAAGGCUGAAAUUAUUCAUUUCUUUUUCUUUUUUUUAAAUAGAGACAGAAUCUCACUAUGUUGCCCAGGCUGGUCUCAAACUCCUGGCCUCAAGUGGUCCUCCUCCCUCAGCCUCCCAAAGUUCUGGUAUUACAGGCUUCAGCCACUGCACCUGGCCUAUUCAUUUGUUUAGUAACAUUUCCAAAUUAGUUUGCAGAGACUGUAUUUCCUACUGGGUAUAAACACUGAAGUCUCUGUUCUUUAGCUUGUGAUCAUGCAGUGUUCUGACAGAGAUUUCCUGACUUUAGCUUGUGUUCAUCCAGCGUUCUGACAGAGAUUUCCUGAAUGUUAGAAGCUAAAAGUAAAAAAGAAGAUGAAACAAACAAAAACCUGACCUCUUCCAGUCUUCAUGGAUGGCUCUCUGCUGGGGCAUUCUUUGAGCACUUAGCCACAGUAUUUACUACUGUAGCCUUCUCUUUCUGUUUAAAUCUGGAUGUUAGCCAGAGCUGAAAAACAGAAUCCCCACCCAUCUUUUAUAAAAAUAUAUUGUUUCCUGUGCCUGCGUGGGGCUUUCUCCAUUCCCCAGUAUAUCUGGGUGCUUUCAAAUAUGCUUAUUUGUAAAGAAAAAUUAUACCCUAGCCUUUUCUCCUGGGACUUAGAUGGUCUAAUAUAUGUCUUUUUUUUUUUUCCUUGAAAUAGUGUCACUCUUUCACUCAGACUUGAGUGCAGUGGCACAAUCGUGGUUCACUGCAGCCUCAACCUCCUAGGCUCAAGCAAUUCUCCUACUUUCCUGAGUAGCUGGGACUACAGGCAUGCGCCACCAUACCCACCUAAUUUUGUUUAUUUUUUGUAGAGAUGAGGUCUCCCCACAUUGCCCAGGCUGGUCUUGAACUCCUUGCCUUUAAGCAAUCUGACCCCCUUGGUGCCGAGACCAGCUCAGUCGUGGAGAGCCUAACCCAGCGGCACUAGAGGAAUUAAAGACACACACACACAGAAAUUUAGAGUGUGGAGUGGGAAAUCAGGGGGCUGACAGCCUUCAGAGCUGAGAGCCACAAACAGAGUUUUACCCACAUAUUUAUUGACAGUAAGCCAGUGAUAAGCGUUGUUUCUAUAGAUUAUAGACUAACUAAAAGCCUUCCUUACGGGAAACAAAGGGAAGGGCUCUGGCUAGUUAUCUGCAGCAGGAACUUGUCCUUAAGGCACAGAUGGCCCAUGCUAUUGUUUGUGGUUCAGGAACGCCUUAAGCAGUUUUCCACCCUGGGUGGGCCAGGUGUUCCUUGCCCUCAUUCCGGUAAACCAACAACCUUCAGCAUGUGCGUCAUAGCCAUCACGAGCAUGUCACAGUGCUGCAGAGAUUUUGUUUAUGGCUAGAUUUGGGGGCCUGUUCCCAACACCUUGGCCUCCCAAAGUACUGGGAUUACAGGUGUGAGCCACCACACCUGGCCUUCUAAUGUAUGUCUUAGUCAUCUUGUGUUGUCCUAGGUGGUUGCACACUUUUUGUGUAUUUUACAACAUUUUAAAGUAGUUCCUGCCCAGUUUGACUCUGAUUGGAUUCUGUUGUAGAUGAAAUAGAAAAGAGAGCCUUGUUUCAGACCUUCGGUUAGUCCCCAGACUGAUUCAAAAAUACAAAGGCAAUAAUGUGGAAACAAAAUGUGAUCUGUACACUCUGUGGUGAUCAGAGUUCUACACUGGGAACUCUGCUGUCUUCAGGACUGGCAAUGAGAUGGGCAGAGAUGGGGCCAAAGAAAAAACAAUACAAGGCUUUUCUAUCAUUUUUCACUUUCCUGUUUAUGUAUCUUUUUCUCUCUGUUAAUAGUAUGGGAUGUGAAAAAUUACAGUUUUAAAUCUUCUGUUUGUUUUUGUAAAGCUGUCUACUUUCUUGAUGAGAAGGUUUUUUUUAAGCAUCUUUAGACAUUUAUGACUUCUAUAAAAAUUGGUUUAUGUAAUGUUAUUGAUUAUUAAAUGUCUGCUGUUGAGAUUUAUGGAAUAUAAUUGAUAUUCAUGAAAGCUGACACUGAAUUCUGUCUAAGAACAUUUGCAGUCUGUCCUCUUCUUUUCUUUCUCCUUCGACAUUACCCAGUAGAAAGUUACAAUUUUUUCUAUUUAGUUGGUAAAAUCUCUUUUAUUAGUCUUUUGUCAUACUUAACUACAUUUGAUCUACAGGGAACCAGUCACCAGCUUCCAAAUAUUCUCUCUGUGUAAUCACGUAGGAUAGGCUAAAUCCCCCAAGUAAGACAUUGAAAAAACAACAACAACAAAAAUAUGAAAUAUCAUCUACCAGAGUUGCACAUUAGGGACCCUGUGCCUAGAGUGUUUCUUUGUGUAUGUCUUAGUCUAUAAGACUGUUUUUUUGUUACUUACAACAGGAUACCAGAACUGGGGUAAUCUAUAAGAAAUGAUAUUUAUUUUUUGCAGUUCUGAAAGCUGGGAAGAUCAAGUAAGGUCAAAGUGGGCAUCUGGUGGGAAUCUUCUUGCUGAUGGGGACUCUGUAGAGUCCCUGGGUGGUACAGGGCAUUACAUGAUGAGGGGGCUGAGUGUCUAGCUGAAGUAUCUUCCUCUUCUCAUAAGGACACCAGAACCUCAUCUGUGAUAACCAGUUUAUUUAUUAAGCCAUUCAUACAUGAGUGGAUUAAUCCAUCCAUGUGUUCCAAACCCUCAAGACCCACUCACCUCUUAAACCACUACCUUUGAUUACUUCCACAUUGGAGAUUCAGUUUCAGCCUGCAUUUUGGAGGGGAAGACAUUCAAACCUAGCAGUGGCUGAUUGGGUACACUUCCUCUGCUGAGGAUGUAAUACAAUUCCAAACUCUCAGAGGGAAGUUAGGAGUUAAGCAAAUACCAUAAUUUUUACACAAAUAGUUUAGGCACACUCCACCCCCUUUAUUAGUUAUGCUUACGGGGCCCUCCCCUAAAUACAUUGUCUAGACACCACGAAAGGUUCAACAUUGUGAACAAGCAGUUGUAAGGAUAUGCCGUCUCAGGACUGCUAAUUGUAACUCUCUUUUGCACAGUAGGUGGUAGGACUUUGUCAUGACAAGGACUACAGACCCACUGUAGAAACAGACAUUAGGAGUAAUCCAGGCAAUAAGAUUCACUUGCAUAAUUCACCAAUAAGAGAUAUGUUCCUACUCAACUGUUAUUUUAGCAAGCCCAAUUCCAGCAUCAGAAUUCCAGCAUCAGACAGUGAGUGCAGACACAGAAUAAGAGUGGAUUUACCACGUCAUUGAAUAAAUGCUUGGAAACCACAGCAUCAUGGGAAGUUUAUGAAGGACUCAGUGGCCUUUGAGGAUGUGGCUGUGAACUUCACCCAUGAGGAGUGGGCUUUGCUGGGUCCAUCACAGAAGAAUCUCUACAGAGAUGUGAUGCGAGAAACCAUUAGGAACCUGAACUGUAUAGGAAUGAAAUGGGAAAACCAGAACAUUGAUGAUCAGCACCAAAAUCUCAGGAGAAAUCCAAGGUGUGAUGUGGUAGAGAGAUUUGGUAAAAGUAAAGAUGGUAGUCAGUGUGGAGAAACCUUAAGCCAGAUUCGAAAUAGUAUUGUAAACAAGAACACUCCCGCCAGAGUAGAUGCAUGUGGAAGCAGUGUGAAUGGAGAAGUCAUAAUGGGUCAUUCAUCCCUGAAUUGCUACAUCAGAGUUGAUACUGGACACAAACACCGGGAGUGUCAUGAAUAUGCAGAGAAGUCAUAUACACAUAAGCAGUGUGGGAAAGGCUUAAGUUAUCGCCACUCCUUUCAAACAUGUGAAAGGCCUCACACUGGAAAGAAACCCUAUGAUUGUAAGGAAUGUGGAAAAACCUUCAGUUCUCCUGGAAACCUUCGAAGACAUAUGGUAGUAAAAGGUGGAGAUGGACCUUAUAAAUGUGAAUUGUGUGGGAAAGCCUUUUUUUGGCCCAGUUUAUUACGUAUGCAUGAAAGAACUCACACUGGAGAGAAACCAUAUGAAUGUAAGCAGUGUUCUAAAGCCUUCCCUGUUUACAGUUCCUAUCUAAGACAUGAAAAAAUACACACUGGGGAGAAACCGUAUGAAUGUAAGCAGUGUUCUAAAGCCUUCCCUGAUUACAGUUCAUAUCUAAGACAUGAAAGAACUCACACUGGAGAGAAACCCUACAAAUGUAAACAAUGUGGGAAAGCCUUCAGUGUUUCCGGUUCCCUUCGAGUACAUGAAAGAAUUCACACUGGAGAGAAACCCUAUACAUGUAAACAGUGUGGGAAAGCGUUUUGUCAUCUUGGAAGCUUUCAAAGACACAUGAUAAUGCACAGUGGAGAUGGACCUCAUAAAUGUAAGAUAUGUGGGAAAGGCUUUGAUUUUCCUGGUUCAGCACGAAUUCAUGAAGGAACUCACACUCUAGAGAAACCCUAUGAAUGUAAGCAAUGUGGGAAAUUGUUAUCUCAUCGCUCAAGCUUUCGAAGACACAUGAUGGCACACACUGGAGAUGGCCCUCAUAAAUGCACAGUAUGUGGGAAAGCCUUUGAUUCUCCUAGUGUAUUUCAAAGACAUGAAAGGACUCACACUGGAGAGAAACCCUAUGAAUGCAAGCAAUGUGGGAAAGCCUUCCGUACUUCCAGUUCCCUUCGAAAACAUGAAACAACACACACUGGAGAGCAACCCUAUAAAUGUAAAUGUGGAAAAGCUUUUAGUGAUUUAUUUUCCUUUCAAAGUCAUGAAACAACACACAGUGAAGAGGAGCCUUAUGAAUGUAAGGAGUGUGGGAAAGCAUUUAGUUCUUUUAAAUACUUUUGUCGCCAUGAAAGGACUCACAGUGAAGAAAAAUCUUAUGAGUGUCAAAUUUGUGGCAAAGCCUUCAGUCGUUUCAGUUACUUAAAAACUCAUGAAAGGACUCACACGGCAGAGAAGCCAUAUGAAUGUAAGCAAUGCAGGAAAGCAUUCUUUUGGCCCUCUUUCCUUCUAAGACAUGAAAGGACUCACACUGGAGAAAGACCCUAUGAAUGUAAACACUGUGGUAAAGCCUUCAGUCGUUCCAGUUUCUGUCGAGAACAUGAAAGAACUCACACUGGAGAGAAGCCCUAUGAAUGUAAGGAAUGUGGGAAAGCCUUCAGUUCUCUCAGUUCCUUUAAUAGACAUAAAAGGACACACUGGAAGGAUAUUCUAUAAGUGUAUGGAAUGUGGGAAAGCAUUCAUUGGUUUUAUCACAUUCAGAUACUUGAAAGAAAUAAAUCCUGUGAAUGUAAACGUGGUAAAGCCUUAAGAAGUUUCCAGGCUGGGCGCAGCGGCUCACACCUGUAAUCCCAGCACUUUGAGAGGCCGAGGAGGGCAGAUCACGAGGCCAGGAGAUCGAGACCAGCCUGGCUAACAUGGGAAACCCUGUCUCUACUAAAAAUACGGAAAAAAAAAAAAAUAGCCAGGCAUAGUUGCUCACACCUGUAGUCCUAGCUACUCAGGAGGCUGAGGCAGGAGAAUCCCUUGAACCCGGGAGGUGGAGGUUGCAGUGAGCCGAGAUUGCACUACUGCACUCCAGCUUGGGUGCUAGAGCGAGACUCCAUCUCAAAAAAAAAAAAAAAAGUUUCCAUUUCUUUCAAAUAGAGUUGCUGCCUGCUAUAUGCAAGAAGAUUGGUUCCAGUACACCCUGAGUAUACCUAAAUCCACAGAUGCCAGCUCUUUUAUAAAAUGGAAUAUUCGCAUGUACCUACCCACAUUCUCCUGUAUACUCUAUAAAUGUCUAGAUUAAUUAAAAUAUCUCAUGCAUUGUAAAA